AGACAAGGUCUUACUUUGUCGCCCAGGCUGUAGUGCAGUAGCACAAUCUCGGCUCACUGCAGCCUCGACCUUUCGGGCUCAAGCAGGGCUCCUCCCUGCUCAGCCUCCCGAGUAGCUGGAACUACAGGCACAUGCACCACACCCGGCUAAUUUUUAAAUUUUUUCGUAGAGAUUGGGGGUCUUGUUAUGUUGCCCAGGUUGGUCUGGAACUCCUGGGCUCAAGUGAUCCUCCUGCCCUGGCCUCCCAAAGUGCUGGGAUUACAGGAGUGAGCCACUGCACCCAACCAGUUACCUCAUUUGUAAAACAGGCAUGGUAACACUUAGUGCAGGAGCAAGAGGAUCAGGGAGCACACAUACAUACAAAGUGCUUGGUGCUGAUGCCCAGCCUGCAGCACCUGUUCUCUAAAUCAUAGCAGCAAUUGCUGCUGCAGCACACUUCUCUUUCUCCUCUCUCCACCGCUCCAUCUCUCCAGGGUCUCUACCUUGCCUGUCAGGCUCCACUUUCCUUUGCUCCUGCCUUUUGCAUCUGUUCCUCUCUGCAUUCUCCCCUCAUCUCCUCUCUUCCGUGCACCUCAUUUUCCUGCUCCCCUCCUGCCUCUGUCCCUCAUCUUCUUUUCAGAGACUUAAAACCAGCCAGUGGCCACUGGCUUUUCAGUGUCUCCUCCUCCUCCUUGAACUACCUCUUCCUUCUAGUGCUUCUGUCCUUCCCUCCUCCUGACCUCCAGUGAACAAUAAUUAUUUGUAACGUAAUGACAAAUUAUCGUUACGUUACAAAGACCAGAGGUUAGAGGUGGUGAUUGGCCUUGUAAACUGUAGGUCAGCGAUGAGUAAUUUAAGAAAACUAAAUUUAAUUGGUUUACUCAUGAGUCAGUUAGGAAUUCUAUUUGGCAGCUAGAACAGAAAUAGCAGUGGCUUAAACCAGUAGAAAUUUUUUCUAUUGUGAAAAGAAAUCUAGGGGGACAGUCUAGGGCUUGUCUCUCCGCUCUGCCAUCCUUAGUGCAGGGCGUCCAACCCCAAGGUUGUAUCAUGGUCUAAGAUGGCUGCGGGAGCCCCAACCAUCAUGUCAGGUUCUAGGAAGAAAGCAGGAAGAAGAGAGGAAAGGCAAAAAGAACACAUGCUCCAUCUUAAGGAGCUUUCCUGCAAGUCCCACCAAAUAGCUUCAGCUUCUCCUCCUUGCCUCCAUUAGUUGCAAGGGAGGCUGAGACAUCAUUUAGCUGAGCACAUUGCUACCUGAGGUAGAAUUGGGAUUCUGUCACCAAGAAAGAAGGGGAGAAUGGAUAUUGUGUAAACAAUUAGCAAGGUCUGCCGCCAUUCAUUCAACAUUAAUUUAGCACCUACAAUCUACUAGUUAUGAAGAACAGUCAAGGUGCCCCAUUCCAGAGGGAAGACAUAGAUAAGUAAACAAGUACAGUACACAGGAUGGGUGAGGAAGAGGGGGAGAGUGGAGAAAGGCAUGAAGUGGGUAUCUUACAUACCCUCCAAGGGCGCAUUCUAGAGUUCGUCAUGCAGACAUUCUUGCCUGUGGUUUGUUUCCUCUUCUGCUCUCUCCUUUUUGUCAUUGUCGCCAUUGUUGUUGUUGGGGUUUGUUUUUGCCCCUCCAUUCUGACGUCAGCAGUAGCCCCUAGAACCUUAGGAAACAGAAACAGUUGGCCUAGUGGGAAGCUCUGGGAUGGGAGCCAUGUGUUUGAAGAGCCAAGUCCCAGGGCCAUUAGGCAAUUAGAGGCCUGUGGCAGGAGAGCAUUCGUUCCUGGACAUGCCGUGGCACUGCCAGGAGACUUUACUCCAGGAAUGGGGUCGUUGUCAGGAGGCAUGUUCUAACCAGGCACCUGGCAUCACCUAUACUGUGCUUGCCAUAAAAUGAAAUUUUGGAGCAGUAAAAUUCUCCAGGUCCCGUGAAAUGGGUAUAAUUGUUUCACCCACAUUAAUUUAACCAGAGGUCUUGGUAUGCUAUAGUGUUAAUUAUGUGUAAAAAUACUUCUACUUACUAUAAAAUGUAUUGACAGUUAGACAUUGAUAUUCCUUCUUAGAACUCAAAAAUUCUAGGAAUAACUUGGGAGACCCACAUUAUCUUUCAUUUUGAUCCCAAGAACAUCUAUUGCUGUUUCCUUUGGGAAGUUAGAGAGGCAAUGGGAAGCCUGCUGCAGAGAUUUUCUAAACAGGCAUAUCCCAGCCCCUAAGGAGUUUGAAAGUGUCAGAGAAGGCUAAAGGAUUAAAAGAUCGUUUGUUCUGGCACAGUGCAAUCCUUAUGAGGUUGUACUGUGACCCUGGGCAAGUUACCAUCCUAUCCUCAGUUUCUUCAUCUGUCAAAUUUUGAUCCUGUGGACCCUCCCCAACAGGGCUGUGAUGGAAAUGAAGAGACACAUGGGAAGCAUUCAGUAUGUGUUGUUGUUAUUAUCAUCAUUAUUGUUAUUUUUAUUAUUAUUAGUGCUACUGGUAGUGCUAGCCCACUAGCCCACUGGGCAGCGACUGCACCCGUAUCAGAGUGUGGAAAGCCUUGGAUGCCACAUUAAGGAGUUGGAUUUUGUGGGCAAGGGUGUGACAGGUCAUGGCUGGGCUUAGAAAUGUCACUGACAGGAGUGGAGAGGCAGAUCUAGGUGAGGAGUGGGCAGGGCUUGAACCUGGCCAGUCAAGGAAAGGGGAGAAUGGAUACCUGAGUGGUGAGGGAGGACCCACUGGUGCUGGAGUUCAGCCUGUGUGCCCAAGGGAUGGUGUCCCAUUGACUUGGGUGGGAAGCACUAGAGGUGGAGCAGUUGGGGUGGCAGGAGGGGAAAGAAGCAUAUGGUGAUCAGCUCAGCAAACAAAUGGGUAACUUGCGCACUCAGUGCUCGGUGGUGCCCAGGCUGGAGUGCAGUGGCGUGGUCCCGGCUCGCUACAACCUCCACCUCCCAGCCGCCUGCCUUGGCCUCCCAAAGUGCUGAGAUUGCAGCCUCUGCCCGGCCGCCACCCCGUCUGGGAAGUGAGGAGCGUCUCUGCUUGGCCACCCAUCGUCUGGGAUGUGGGGAGCCCCUCUGCCUGGCUGCCCAGUCUGGGAGGUGAGGAGCGUCUCCGACCGGCCGCCAUCCCAUCUAGGAGGUGAGGAGCGCCUCUUUCCGGCCGCCAUCACAUCUAGGAAGGAGGAGCGUCUCUGCCCGGCCGCCCAUCGUCUGAGAUGUGGGGAGCGCCUCUGCCCCGCCGCCCCGUCUGGGAUGUGAGGAGCACCUCUGCCCGGCCACGACCCCGUCUGGGAGGUGAGGAGCAUCUCUGCCCCGCCGCCCCGUCUGAGAAGUGAGGAGACCCUCUGCCCGGCAACCACCCCGUCUGAGAAGUGAGGAGACCCUCCACCCGGCAGCUGCCCCGUCUGAGAAAUGAGGAGCCUCUCCGCCCGGCAGCCACCCCGUCUGGGAAGCUGAUGGGAACCACCCUGUAGAGGUCCAUCUGCGUUCAGACCCAGACGAUGCCAGAGCUAUGACUGGGCCUGCAGGUGUGGCGCCGAGGGGAGAUCAGCCAUGGAGCAGCCACAGGAGGAAGCCCCUGAGGUCCGGGAAGAGGAGGAGAAAGAGGAAGUGGCAGAGGCAGAAGGAGCCCCAGAGCUCAAUGGGGGACCACAGCAUGCACUUCCUUCCAGCAGCUACACAGACCUCUCCCGGAGCUCCUCGCCACCCUCACUGCUGGACCAACUGCAGAUGGGCUGUGACGGGGCCUCAUGCGGCAGCCUCAACAUGGAGUGCCGGGUGUGCGGGGACAAGGCAUCGGGCUUCCACUACGGUGUUCAUGCAUGUGAGGGGUGCAAGGGCUUCUUCCGUCGUACGAUCCGCAUGAAGCUGGAGUACGAGAAGUGUGAGCGCAGCUGCAAGAUUCAGAAGAAGAACCGCAACAAGUGCCAGUACUGCCGCUUCCAGAAGUGCCUGGCACUGGGCAUGUCACACAACGCUAUCCGUUUUGGUCGGAUGCCGGAGGCUGAGAAGAGGAAGCUGGUGGCAGGGCUGACUGCAAACGAGGGGAGCCAGUACAACCCACAGGUGGCCGACCUGAAGGCCUUCUCCAAGCACAUCUACAAUGCCUACCUGAAAAACUUCAACAUGACCAAAAAGAAGGCCCGCAGCAUCCUCACCGGCAAAGCCAGCCACACGGCGCCCUUUGUGAUCCACGACAUCGAGACAUUGUGGCAGGCAGAGAAGGGGCUGGUGUGGAAGCAGUUGGUGAAUGGCCUGCCUCCCUACAAGGAGAUCAGCGUGCACGUCUUCUACCGCUGCCAGUGCACCACAGUGGAGACCGUGCGGGAGCUCACUGAGUUCGCCAAGAGCAUCCCCAGCUUCAGCAGCCUCUUCCUCAACGACCAGGUUACCCUUCUCAAGUAUGGCGUGCACGAGGCCAUCUUCGCCAUGCUGGCCUCUAUCGUCAACAAGGACGGGCUGCUGGUAGCCAACGGCAGUGGCUUUGUCACCCGUGAGUUCCUGCGCAGCCUCCGCAAACCCUUCAGUGAUAUCAUUGAGCCUAAGUUUGAAUUUGCUGUCAAGUUCAACGCCCUGGAACUUGAUGACAGUGACCUGGCCCUAUUCAUUGCGGCCAUCAUUCUGUGUGGAGACCGGCCAGGCCUCAUGAACGUUCCACGGGUGGAGGCUAUCCAGGACACCAUCCUGCGUGCCCUCGAAUUCCACCUGCAGGCCAACCACCCUGAUGCCCAGUACCUCUUCCCCAAGCUGCUGCAGAAGAUGGCUGACCUGCGGCAACUGGUCACCGAGCACGCCCAGAUGAUGCAGCGGAUCAAGAAGACCGAAACCGAGACCUCGCUGCACCCUCUGCUCCAGGAGAUCUACAAGGACAUGUACUAACGGCGGCACCCAGGCCUCCCUGCAGACUCCAAUGGGGCCAGCACUGGAGGGGCCCACCCACAUGACUUUUCCAUUGACCAGCCCUUGAGCACCCGGCCUGGAGCAGCAGAGUCCCACGAUCGCCCUCAGACACAUGACACCCACGGCCUCUGGCUCCCUGUGCCCUCUCUCCCGCUUCCUCCAGCCAGCUCUCUUCCUGUCUUUGUUGUCUCCCUCUUUCUCAGUUCCUCUUUCUUUUCUAAUUCCUGUUGCUCUGUUUCUUCCUUUCUGUAGGUUUCUCUCUUCCCUUCUCCCUUGCCCUCCCUUUCUCUCUCCACCCCCCACGUCUGUCCUCCUUUCUUAUUCUGUGAGAUGUUUUGUAUUAUUUCACCAGCAGCAUAGAACAGGACCUCUGCUUUUGCACACCUUUUCCCCAGGAGCAGAAGAGAGUGGGGCCUGCCCUCUGCCCCAUCAUUGCACCUGCAGGCUUAGGUCCUCACUUCUGUCUCCUGUCUUCAGAGCAAAAGACUUGAGCCAUCCAAAGAAACACUAAGCUCUCUGGGCCUGGGUUCCAGGGAAGGCUAAGCAUGGCCUGGACUGACUGCAGCCCCCUAUAGUCAUGGGGUCCCUGCUGCAAAGGACAGUGGGCAGGAGGCCCCAGGCUGAGAGCCAGAUGCCUCCCCAAGACUGUCAUUGCCCCUCCGAUGCUGAGGCCACCCACUGACCCAACUGAUCCUGCUCCAGCAGCACACCUCAGCCCCACUGACACCCAGUGUCCUUCCAUCUUCACACUGGUUUGCCAGGCCAAUGUUGCUGAUGGCCCCCUGCACUGGCCGCUGGACGGCACUCUCCCAGCUUGGAAGUAGGCAGGGUUCCCUCCAGGUGGGCCCCCACCUCACUGAAGAGGAGCAAGUCUCAAGAGAAGGAGGGGGGAUUGGUGGUUGGAGGAAGCAGCACACCCAAUUCUGCCCCUAGGACUCGGGGUCUGAGUCCUGGGGUCAGGCCAGGGAGAGCUCGGGGCAGGCCUUCCGCCAGCACUCCCACUGCCCCCCUGCCCAGUAGCAGCCGCCCACAUUGUGUCAGCAUCCAGGGCCAGGGCCUGGCCUCACAUCCCCCUGCUCCUUUCUCUAGCUGGCUCCACGGGAGUUCAGGCCCCACUCCCCCUGAAGCUGCCCCUCCAGCACACACACAUAAGCACUGAAAUCACUUUACCUGCAGGCUCCAUGCACCUCCCUUCCCUCCCUGAGGCAGGUGAGAACCCAGAGAGAGGGGCCUGCAGGUGAGCAGGCAGGGCUGGGCCAGGUCUCCGGGGAGGCAGGGGUCCUGCAGGUCCUGGUGGGUCAGCCCAGCACCUGCUCCCAGUGGGAGCUUCCCGGGAUAAACUGAGCCUGUUCAUUCUGAUGUCCAUUUGUCCCAAUAGCUCUACUGCCCUCCCCUUCCCCUUUACUCAGCCCAGCUGGCCACCUAGAAGUCUCCCUGCACAGCCUCUAGUGUCCGGGGACCUUGUGGGACCAGUCCCACACCGCUGGUCCCUGCCCUCCCCUGCUCCCAGGUUGAGGUGCGCUCACCUCAGAGCAGGGCCAAAGCACAGCUGGGCAUGCCAUGUCUGAGCGGCGCAGAGCCCUCCAGGCCUGCAGGGGCAAGGGGCUGGCUGGAGUCUCAGAGCACAGAGGUAGGAGAACUGGGGUUCAAGCCCAGGCUUCCUGGGUCCUGCCUGGUCCUCCCUCCCAAGGAGCCAUUCUGUGUGUGACUCUGGGUGGAAGUGCCCAGCCCCUGCCCCUACGGGCGCUGCAGCCUCCCUUCCAUGCCCCAGGAUCACUCUCUGCUGGCAGGAUUCUUCCCGCUCCCCACCUACCCAGCUGAUGGGGGUUGGGGUGCUUCCUUUCAGGCCAAGGCUAUGAAGGGACAGCUGCUGGGACCCACCUCCCCCUCCCCGGCCACAUGCCGCGUCCCUGCCCCGACCCGGGUCUGGUGCUGAGGAUACAGCUCUUCUCAGUGUCUGAACAAUCUCCAAAAUUGAAAUGUAUAUUUUUGCUAGGAGCCCCAGCUUCCUGUGUUUUUAAUAUAAAUAGUGUACACAGACUGACGAAACUUUAAAUAAAUGGGAAUUAAAUAUUUAA